AGAGAUAGAGCUUCGCGGAGACGGCGGAAGCGGAGAGCAACAGCGCGCCGGUAACAACCAGCCCCGUAUCCCCUCCCUCUGUACCUCAAGCUAGGAUUUUUAAUCCCCACUUCUCCCUUCACAGCCCGGGACAAGACUUCCAUUCCGUCGUUUGUUGCUGGUAUUUUUUUUCCUCAUGUGACGCGAGGGGCCGCCCCCUGCCUGGGGCGGAGGUUACUGGGAAGCUCCCGCCUUCUGACCCCUGCGGGCCCGCGGUUGAGAGGGACCCUCCCGGGGCUCUUUUGCACUCACUGGGGCUCGUGCUCGCUUUGGGCGCUCGCCCCAAAUGAUCCUGGCGGAAAGGACGUGCUUUUUCUGGGUUUCAACAGAGACGGAGUUUUGCCAUGUUGUCCAGGCUGGUGUCGAAAUCCUGAGCUCAAGUGGUCUGCCUGCCUCGGCUUCCCAAAGUGCUGGGAUUACAGGUGAGGCUGCUGUCAGAAAGGAACUUUUACACAGUUUGCCUUCAGAGACAGUCUAUCGGCAUGUUGUAGAGUUUUAUUACUAAGAAAAUAAAUGUUACUUACAUGGGAUAAAAGCAGCAUAUGAAAGAUACUAUCUGCCCUCAAGAAACUUGUAGAGUGUGAGAUGGCAUUCAUAAAUGAAACAGUUGAAUAAGAAUAUAAAGGAGUAUAUAAUGAGAGUGAUAUAACAACAAUGAGAUGUCUCAGUUUAAACACAACUCAUUUAGGAGGGCGUUAGACAUUAUCAAGGAGGGCAUUUCAGAAGUUGGAAGGAGCAGACAAUGAGGCCAUCCUGCCCAGAAUGGAGACUUUGUGUCUGAGAAUGAUAGAAGUAUUAUUGAAAUUGUAGAUUGACACCAAAUCAUGGAAAAUCUUAAAUGCAAGAUGGUUUUACUCAGCAUUUGGUGUGGUGGAUCUUACAUAAACCUUUAGAACUUACAUUAGAGUGUUCAAGUCUUCUGAGACUCCAGAGUCACCUAAGAUUGUGGUGGUGCCAUGCAGCAAGAAUCAGAGAGAUGCAGAGUUAGAGCCAGAAGGCCUGACAUGGCACUUUAUGUACCUAAAGCUCGUAGGGGUGCAGUACUCCUUAAGACAGGUGAUGAAGAAGAAAGCUGUGGUUCACCUAACUCUGUGGUGAAAGAAAAGCAAAAAGAAAGUUCUCUCUCCCAAAAAGAAGUCUUUAAAGACAAACCGGAGGCUCGAAGACUAAAUAUCAAUCCUGAUAGAAAGGAGCAUAAUUGUAGAGAAGAAAAGAAAUCUUCAACAAAAUUAAGAAUGGACACAUGCCUUCAAAAAACAAAUAGAGUUUGUUCUAAGAGAGGAACCACUGAAUCCAAAGAAGUAUUAUCCCAAGGACAACAGCAGGGAGCCCCAAAUGCUGGGGUUAUAACUAAUGCACCUUUGCAGAGACAUUUUAAACCAAAGAAGGUGGAGUGUUUGGAAGUUGAAACUACGGAUGUGACAGGACAUGAGAGGAUACUUCUUUCACAGGCCUGUUUAGAAAUCAGCGAGGCUCAAGUUCCAAGCAAACCAUUCCAAAAUGUGGAAUUCUGUGACUUCAGUAGGCAUGAACCUGAUGGGGAAGCAUUUGAAGACAAAGAUUUGGAAGGCAGAAUUGAAACUGAUACCAAGGUUUUGGAGAUACUAUAUGAGUUUCCUAGAGUUUUUAGUUCUGUCAUGAAACCUGAGAAUAUGAUUGUACCAAUAAAACUAAGCUCUGAUUCUGAAAUUGUACAACAAAGCAUGCAAACAUCAGAUGGAAUAUUGAAUCCCAGCAGCGGAGGCAUCACCACUACUUCUGUUCCUGGAAGUCCAGAUGGUGUCUUUGAUCAAACUUGCGUAGAUUUUGAAGUUGAGAGUGUAGGUGGUAUAGCCAAUAGUACAGGUUUCAUCUUAGAUCAAAAAGAUACAGAUUCCAUUCCUGCAACUAUGGGUCACAUCUCUCUGUCAGAGAGCACAAAUGACACUGUUAGUCCAGUAAUGAUUAGAGAAUGUGAGAAGAAUGACAGCACUGCUGAUGAGUUACAUGUAAAGCACGAACCUCCUGAUACAGCUGUCCUUGCUCAUGAAACACAUAGAGAUAGUGGAUUUAAGAAUGUAGGUGACAUUACCAAUAAAGCAUGUAUGAUGGACACUACAGGUAUGUCCUGUAGUGAUCAUGUAACUGUUGAUAGCCCUUAUGUAGUUGCAGUUAGAAUAGCUGAUGAGACCUCUAUUAAUACACGAAGUUUCUCAAAGUUUGUAGGAAUGAGUGCAGAUGCAACCCCUCUUCAUGUAGCUAGAAGUGGGAAUGACACUGAAGAUUUCAGCAACCCUUCUGCUUGCUCAGAUAUUUAUGGUGAGAGUAUUUCAUCUCAUUUUACAGAGUCAACAGGAAAGUUGAUAGAGAGCUUGUCAGAUUGUGCUUCCUCCUUACCUAUAAAAAAGAUUGCUGGUAGUAAUUAUAACACUUUUUUGGACUCUGAACUCAGUAUGUUAAAUGGGACAAAAGUUCUUUCAGACAGUGCCGUGGGCAUUGACCUGGGUAGUACUGGUGAUACAACAGAAGCAUUGCACGAACUAAGAACUGCCGAAGAGUUCAAAACAGAAGAGCAAGAUGACUCAGGGAGUAUAGAAUUUGGUGUAUCUUUUCCUGAUAGGGAAUCAUCAUCUAUGGAAACAUCCAUCGAACCAAAAGCAACUGAAACUUCUCACACAGAGGGAAUUACUGCCAUUGAGGAGAGCUGGGAGUCUAUGUUUAACGAUGAUGGUGACUGCCUGGAUCCACGUCUUCUACAAGAGUUAUCAGGGAAUACCAAGAGCAGAGAGAGCAUCCAGGAACCUAGAUCUGAUUACUACAAUCAUGAAGUUCCUGAUAUUGACCUCAGUGAUUGUGAAUUCCCACAUGUCAUUGAAAUUUAUGACUUUCCCCAAGAAUUUCAUACUGAAGACCUUCUACGGGUUUUCUGCAGUUAUCAAAAGAAAGGAUUUGAUAUUAAAUGGGUGGAUGAUACACAUGCCCUAGGAGUAUUCUCCAGUCCAAUUACAGCUCGUGAUGCGUUGGGUAUUAAACACACCAUGGUGAAGAUUCGUCCCUUGUCACAGGCCACAAGAGCAGCCAAGGCCAAAGCUAGAGCUUAUGCUGAGUUCCUCCAGCCAGCAAAGGAGCGUCCUGAGACUUCAGCAGCCCUAGCCAGAAGGUUAGUCAUCAGUGCCCUUGGGGUUCGAAGUAAGCAGAGCAAAACCGAACGAGAAGCAGAGCUCAAGAAACUGCAAGAAGCCAGAGAGAGAAAGCGGUUGGAAGCCAAGCAACGGGAAGACAUCUGGGAAGGCAGAGACCAGUCUACAGUUUGAACAUCACUCAAUGAAAGGGAUAAUUCCAUGAAUCAGAAAAUGUUUCCAUAGCCUUCAGAUAAGAUGAUCCUUCCAGAGCUCUAUGUACAUGCAGAUGUGCAUGUUAAAGAGAUAAAGUGAUCGAGACAAGGACUGACUGGGUAUAGAAGGAAGACAGACUCCUGUCUUCACUCCUAAAUGCAGUUCUUUGGAAUCACCCUACUGUGGUGGGCGUAGUAGGGAGCCAUCAGCUAGGAAGAAACGUGGGAGAUGUGAAUUCCAAGAGUUGCCUGGACAGGGCAAGUCAUGUUAGCGUGGGUCACACUUCCAAGAUAUUUAAAGCAAAUACAAAACAGAACAGAGGAUUCAAACCGCAAGUAUGGGAGAUUUAGGCCCUGCAGAGGCAGACCAUUCCUUAGUAUCUCACAAAGCAGAGUAAUACUGGAGGCAGAGUAGGGGGUGGUUGGAGAGCAGUUAGUACAAAGAGGCAGAACAGUGUCUGGUUUACUUGGCAUACACAGAAUCUGCACUGCCGGUUCCAGAACUGCAAAGUUGGUGAACUACAGGAGAUGUGGGUAUUUAGACUCCAAAGUUUAUACUGAGCUCAGUGCCUGGGACCGCUCCAGCUGCACUGCAGCCAGGGGGGAUACCAGCUUCAUUCCUCAGAGUAAACCAACCUUGGGAGCUGUGUGCCAGUUCCAGUGUAAGCAGUAAUACCAUGUUGUAAGAGGGAACAUUAAAGCCCAUUUUAUGACAUAUA